UGGCCCCACCCCGGGAUCCGGGGAGGCUGAUCCCCCACGGGCCUCUCCCAACCUGAGCAGCGCCCUCCUGGCCACUGUCCACUGCUGCCUGAGGCCCUGCCCCAGCAGAAGGCACAGGCUGGGACAGGCCUGCAAGAAUGGCCAGGAGGGGCCUCCCAGGGUCGAGGCAUCUGAGCAGCACCCUGCAGGACGGGCAGGCCCCUCAUGCCCCGGGCACCUGCACAGGGCCUGCGAUCUCAUGCAUUCGAAUGGUGCCGAAUGGGCCAGGGUGUCCUGGGGGAUCCUGUCGGGCGCCCUCCUCAGCUCUUCCACUUUCCACAGCGGCCUGGCCGGGAGGCAAGCACAGUUCCCACUACUUGGUCCCAGCUCCCCAGCUCCGGGCAUUCAGAUGGGCUCGUGGCCACCAGGCCGUUGGGUCCAAGUGAGGACUUGGUGCCCAGCACCUUCCUGUGCAAGAAGUCAGGGAGUUCAAGACGAGAUCAAGGCUGAUCCAGGCCUUGCGCGGCUCCUGCUCACAGGAUCCUGGGGACCGUUUCAAGAAGAGCCUCAGGACACGGAGAAUGCUCAGUCUCCUGGCUCUCCCCGCCAGGCAAGAGGGCCCGGGGGUGGAGGGAAUCCAGGGGACACAGUCCUCACCCCACUGUCAGCGCCAGCAGACCCCAACACUCAUCCCCCAGCCCCAGGCACACAACCCGCCCUGCCGCCCCUCGCCAGGCCCUGCCGGGUGUCCACCCUCUGCGGCAGCAGGUUGGGGAGGAGACGUGCUGGGGAGGGGCCCAGGCCUGGGCGGGCGCUGCCCUUCCUUUCACUCCCCUGCCAGGCAGUGCCUGCGCCCACCCUCACCCCCACCCCCCCUGACCCCCCGCGGGCUGGGAGGAAAUGUAAUGAGCGCAGGGCGGUGUCUUUGGUGCUGCUGGGGUGGAGUCAGGGGCCAGAUCCCAUCGUGAAUUUGACAGAAAAGGAAAUGGGCUCCGAGCGCAGGUGAGGCUCAGCCAGGGCUCCGUGGCUCUCACCCAAGAGCUGAGCUCCAACCUUCCUGGCCCGGCUCCGUUUCCCGAGCUGUGGAAAAUGCCUGUCCACCCGGAUUGGCUGGGUAGUGCCUGCCUCCCCCACGCCAGUCCUCUGUGGGAGGGUUGCUGGUCUCUGUUAAAAGCCCCCCGGGUGACGUGCAUGCUGCCAGGGCCUGUGCCCCCGGUAGACACUCUGGGGAGGGGCCACCACAAGGAAACCUCAGUCCAAGCUGUCCAGCGGAGGCUGGGCAUGGCUGUGCCAGCACAGGAAGGCAGGUAGGGGUCUCUGGGGCAGGCAGCUCUCCCCCUGGCCCAGCCCCCUGUGUGAAGUGCUCAGCCUGGGUAGGAACGUGCUUCCCACUCAGCCUCCUCCAAGCCGCUGGAGGUCCCACUGGUUCCCCAAAUGGCUUCUGUCCUGAGCCGUGGGCUCCUGACCACGCAUCUACCUUGCACGGUCUGAACAAGAGUCUGCGCCAGGGACCCCGAUCGGGAGGGGCACAGAGGAAGCCAAGGGCCCACACAGGUGAGGGGGUCUCGGGUCUGAGCCUCACCCAGCCCAGGCUCAGCAGCAGCCUCAGAAUUUCCUGGCAUCUGCUUGCCUGUGUUGCAACCCAAGUGGGAUGUGCACGCCGCCUGAGAGAGAAAACACUCGGGGAGGAUUAUGUAAGCGCUUUCCUCCCCAGCACAGGGCCGUCCUGGGCACAUUGAGGCCAGACCAUGUGCAAAAGCACUCGGGAGAGUGGCAGGAGCUGAGCCACCAGAGGGGGAUUAACCCCUUCCGGGAUGCUGGCAGCUUGUCCUGGGGAACAUGGGGCUGGUCAGGAUUGCAGGACACGGAGGGGCGGAGUGUGAAUGUGGAGGCACCGGUGCUGCGUGAUUUUCCACAAGUUGUCUAACCUCUCUGUGCCUUCAUUGCCUGACUCGGCUGUUUCCAAUGCAACUGAUUUUAACGGCACCUGUUUCAUGAGGCCACAGCCAGGAUUCUGGGAGGCAAAGCACAGAAAGCCCUCAAUGCGGUUUCAGGCUCCAGGCAAGGCUCAGCUGACAGUAGCUGAAAACAGCAAUUUCAGCCGCAGAGUUGCCCGCCCUGUGCACCACAGAACGAACAAGGGUUUCCAGCUUUGCUCAGAUUUGUGGGGACCACUGGGUUUGGACUUUAGGAAAAGCUCAUUUGCCUUUAGGCAGAAGUGACCGGAGCUGGGGUCACCUGAGGUCUGGGCAGGAACCUCUCGAUGGCUGAUGCAGGACCUGGGGAGGGGCCAUCUGUGUGGGGCAGCUCUGGACUCAGACCCGUGGAUACCUGUGAAACCUGUCAGGCUGAGCCACCAUCCAGCAAGUGAAGAGACCGCAACUGGGCCACUGUGGAGUCACUUGGCCACCACCCCCGGGUCCUCAUAGCCCUCAUGUGUGUCCCAACCGCGAGCAGGUGGCCGACAGUGCACCCUGACAAGGCACGUGUGUACCAUCGGGGACACCUGCUUCUUUAAAGUGACCGGAUGGUGCCCAGGACCACAAGAACCAGCCUCGUGGCAGGGUGCCCAGCCUCCUUCCCCCUCCACUGUUAACUUUUUUGCCAAGAUUCCAAAAACGAAGCUGCAGCUGAAAAUAAUUUCUUUUUCUUCUAUAGCCCAAAUGACCGAUGGUGUAGAGAUUUUCCCAUCAUAGAACUGCAGUCUCCAUUUGUAGUAGGCCCAGACAGUGACAUGUCUGAGGUUGGGGUGCCUUGGGGCCAGAGCCCAGAGGAGAACCCACAUUGGCGUCCUAGUAAUGUGAACCCUCAUAAGAGCUUCAGGACAGCAGAGGCAGUGGAGAUGCCGGCGGGCAGGGAGAGCCGGCCCGGCCAGCCCCCUGGGAAUAAGCUUCAGUCCUAUUCUAACUCAAAAUCAUAAACCUCAUCUCAGGCGGCUGCUUGUGACUCCAAGAGACCACCAGGCCCCGGUGAUAGCCAGCACAGUACCUGGCACAUAAAUCCUGCCCACCUGCCUGGCGUGGCUGGGAGACCCGCCCGGGUGCUCUCUGUCUCUCCCUCCCUCUUUCACUGCUCCCUGAAGGCAGCGUCUAAAGAGGCUGAGGCUGUCCUGUCACUGCCCCGACCUCUGAGGAGAAGCCCGCGGCUGUCCUGUCACUGCCCCGACCUCUGCGGAGAAGCCCGCAGUUCUGAUCACGGACCUCAGAUGGGGAAGCGCACAGGAGGCCUCGGGUGGCCGGGCUGUGCUGCUUCUCCCUAGACGGGCAGAGCUGGCGCAUAGGAGGUGCUUCACAGGUGACUAAGGAGGCAAAGACCCGAAGCCUGGGGGACUGCAGUGUCCGGUGGAUCCCAGCUGCGGCCAUCGGGCCCAUGGGUGGGAGAGCCAAGGGAGGGGCUCAGCUGGGCAAUAGGAUGGGAGUGGGCGGGGGACACUGCUGGGAACUCCCUUCACUGCAUGGCCAAGACUGUGCAUAAGCGAACAGGGCGGGAGAGCUGUGUGUCGCCUCGGGCAGUCACUCAGCCUCUCCGCCCGUUUUCCUGGUCUGUAAAAUGGGCCGAAAUGCCCUCCCUGCGCUGUUCUUUGGGCAGUUUCUAUAAAUGCUUGGCCCAGCCUCCCCGGCACACGGUUGCUACCUGGAUCACUGUUCUGUUAUUUUCAUCCCUGCCCCUGCUCUUUGCUUAGACCGACUUCCCCUGACUCCGGUGAAAUCAGCCUCCACAGGCAUUUCAUCAGCCCUUGUUCGUCCACAACACGGCUAGGCAGGUGUGCUCAGGGGGUCUGAGGCUUUCACAGACGUUAAAUGUAUGUCCCUGCAGGAAACAGGUUUCUGUACAGCCCCAGAGACUGUACAGAAGGCUGAGGCCAUCUCUACUAAAAAUACAAAAAAAUUAGCCGGGUGUGGUGGCAGUUUUUCUUUGUGACAAGAUAUAGGUAAGAUUUCUGAAAGACAGGAGCUAGUAACAUGUUCUAUUUCUUCUGAUAGCAGUUUUUUCCUAGUAAUUUGUCAAUUGCAUUUAACGUUUCCCACUGACUUUUGAGACAGCCUCAAGUUUUUAUGUCUGAAGGGUUCGUAGAUUCUGACAUUGUAAUUUGUCCCUGCUCUCUUUUCUCUGACUAGUGUACCAGGGCUUUCUCAAGUGUACUAAUCUUCUCAAAGAAUCCAAUUUGGUUUUGUUGGUUGUAUCUACUCUACGUUUUGUGCCUCAUUUCCUUAAUUUUUCCUUGUCUUUAAGCUUUUCUCUAAUACAACUGUCGAUGUAUUCCCCGA